CUGAACCAAAUGAAGAGGAUCUGGAAGGCAAAGCACUAAGAUCAUAGUGAAGACUUGCCUCCCCCUUCUCCUUGUGUCCCACCAGCCUCCCUGCUGGCCUGACCAGGCCCCAUACUCCAGUCUCCCCAGAGACCCCAAGCUGAAGAUUCUGUGGGUCUGCCCCAUUGCUGGGCACAGCAGAGCCUGGAUGGAGGCUUGUUGUCUUCUGCAGUUGCCCCAAAGGUUGCUCUUGCUGGGGGCAGCCGCCCUGACUGCAACUGCUUUGGAGACAGCCGACCUGGCGGAACUGUGCGGGCAGACGUGGCAGGGGGACGGGCUGCUGCUGCGCUCGCACGCCGCAUCGCGCAGGUUCUACUUCGUGGCUCCGGACACCGACUGCGGGCUCUGGGUGCAGGCGGCAGCCCCCGGCGACCGGAUCCGCUUCCAGUUCCGCUUCUUCCUGGUCUACAGCCUGACCCCCGCGCCCCCGGCGCUCAACACCUCCUCCCCGGCCCCGGCCGACCCGUGCGCCCCCGGCUCCUACCUGCAGUUCUACGAGGGCCCGCCGGGGGCGCCCCGGCCCCUGGGGUCCCCACUGUGCGGCCUGAACAUCCCGGUGCCUGUGGCAUCCUCCGGACCCUUUCUAGGCCUGCGCCUGGUCACGAGAGGCCGCCAGCCCCGCGUGGACUUCGUGGGCGAAGUCACCUCUUUCCGUCUGGGACCUUGUGGUGCCUACUUCCGCUGCCAGAAUGGCAGGUGCAUCCCCUCAAGCCUCGUGUGUGACCCCUGGGGCAUGGACAACUGUGGCGAUGGCAGUGACCAGGGCUCCUGGUCACCAGCUGACUGCAGAGGUCCCUCUCCGGUGCCCAGCCAGACAGGAAGUACAGAUGCCCAUACCUCCAGAUCCCUGACUCCCUCCCCAGCUCUCGGGUCUGCAGGAUCCCUCUGGAUUGCAGCUGAGAGGAGUUCCCCAGCAGGCAGGGACCCCACGAGACAAGACGCAGCUUUGGAAGGCUCCACUGAGUGAAGCCCUCAUCAAAGACUCAGGAGGCCCCUGGCGGGGAUAGCACCGUUUAUUAAGAAAAAUCAAGACAAAGACCACAGGAGGGUCCCUUCUAGGACACAGAGGCCAGGCGUCCCAACCCCACAGUCUGGGGGCCACUGGCAGGAUGGCACUUGAGCUGGAUCUUCAGGCUCCUGCAGAUGGGGCAGGGUGGUCAUAUCCCCCUCCUCUCUCUCUCAGUCGUGAGUCCUGCCUUCCCCCACCUAAGGCACUAGCUCUUCCUGAGCACCAGCGGCAUCCGUCCGUCCGUUGUCUGUUGGAGGAGUCCCUGGGCCUUCACUUCCAGAUGGGUGGGGAUGUGGCCUGGGGUGGGCGGGGCCCGGUGGGCGGGGCCCUAUCAGUGCUGGGCUCUGCCUGUAGCAGCUCCUGGUAAGAGUUGGGGUGGGCCUUCCCUUACAGCCCCUGAGGGAGGGACCCCAGGCUGUGUGCUGGCAGGAGGGGGUGGGAAUGCAGGCCAGGAGGACGUGGUAGGAGGGGGAGUCUGCCAGAGGAGGUGCCAGGGGCUGGGUGGAGGUGGGUGGGGGUGCUGAAAAACGAGCUGGUGGGGAUGGGGACCGCCUGCCCAGGGGUGAGCUGCCUUUUGCUCCACAGCCGGCACUAAAGACAAUUCCCAAUCCUGAGUGGGUGGCAGAGACUCCUGCGAUGCCCGUCUCAGGUAGCUGUGGGGCACCAGCCCACAAGCCGAGGUUGGCUCUCCUAGGAGUGAGAACUGCCCAAGGGCUGCAGAAACAGGCCACCCAGCUCUAUCUGGGGGCUCCAUCGGUGGGUAGGGGGACAGUGGGGGCAGUUCUGGGCCCACCCAGCCACUGUUCCUGACCCCAAGUCCUGGUGACUUUCUGAGGUGCCCACUCCCAUCCAACCUGCCUUGCUGGCCAGCCUUGUGGCUUUGCCCAGCUGUGUGUGUGAGGGUGGCAUGCCCACCUCCAGUCCAGCCCAGGGCGGUAGCAGCAAAGCGUGGCAUCGCCUCGGUUUCUUACAAAAAUUCAUAAUAAUAUUAAUAAUAAUAUACUCGACAUUGUCGGGCUGGGGCGUGGCCCGGGAGUCCGUGUGGGGCAGGCAGGUGCCUACGAGGGGCAGGGGCGUGUGUUGGCCCCGGCCUGGGCGCGGUGCUGCAGGUCCAGGGGCUGUGGGGGCGGGGCGCCGGGUCGGGCCGAGUGCAGCACCAGGUUCUUGACACAGCCUGUGAUGCCUGAGGAGAAUCUGCCCCCGGUCAGCGUGGCCACGUCAGGGGCUCCGCCUGCCGGGAGGUGAGAGGACAGGGCCUGUGGGCUCCAGCAGCCCAGGAGGCGAGGAAGGCUGGGCGAGCUCUAGCCCUAAGGGAGUGCCGUUCCUGCCCCUGCCCUGAGAAGGAGCCCCAGACUUACCGAUGUAGACGCUGCCCUUGGCGUUGACUGCCACGUUGGGACCUGGGGACCGGCCGCUGACCAGCUCCUCACCGUCGACUUGGAUGGAACCUCUGCGGCCCUCCCUGCAGUGGAACUGGGUCAGGCCCCUUUCCACAAACUUCCUGGUCCUCCCCGGCCCCACGACAGAGUCCCCUCCCUCUGAUAUCGAGACUCCAGACUCAGAAGUCUGUCCCUGUUUCCCAAGCUCUUUCUUUCCCCCGCUGAACGAGAGAUCGGGCCCCACAAACACAGCUUCCUCAUUUCUGCACCCAGGUUUCCUCCCACUCCUGGGGCACUCGCCUGCCCCCAGCGGAGUUCAGUCCGAGAUGGAAGCCCGAGCCCUGGCUGGUGGGUUCUCCCCUCCCCUGGCUUCAAGUUCUGUCUCCACAGAGCUCAAUACCUGCCUCUCUGCCCAUGGUAGGGGGCGUCCUGCCCCACUCCAGAACGCUGGGCCCCAUCCCGAGUGCCCGGCAGGGUCCCUUACCGCAGUGCUGUCACCCGGUGCCACUCGCCGUCAUUGAUGGGGUCCUCAGAGACCAGGCGGGCCUCCCCACUACCCAGCUGGUACCUGCAGUCAUCCAGGCCCAAGAAGUAUGAGCUGGGGCAGGACCGGGGGGUGGGGUGCUGGGACCAGGGAAGGGAGAGGAAGGGCCAGGUGCCAGGACCUACCUGAAGACAAGGUGCCCGUCUUGAAGCCCGAGGCUGAUGAAGUCCUUGCCUUGGCCGGCCUCUCCCACCUCCUGCCAGGGAAGCACAGGGUCUCUGGGGUCCCCAGCCUGGAGAGCAGAGGCUGCCGAGGCCAGGGGGCUCUGCUUUCCCCUCCCCCCACCACUCCGGCCACCAGGAAGCCAGCUUCCUGCCCCAGGAGCCCCAAGAGCCCAGCCGGAUACCCACACUCACCACACCCUGCCAGAGCAGGAGGCCACUGGCUGUGCUGGUCCGAACCUCCAGCUCGAUGGUCUCGGGCACCUCGGGCAGGCUGCGGAGGAAGAGCGGGUGAGGGGACAGAAGUCCCAGAUUCCCAUCCUCCCCAUUAGGCCCAUGGGCCCUUCCAAUGCCAGUCUCACCUCCUGGAGAAGACAUGGCCAGGGAAGGCGAGGAAGCCAUCAUCGUGGAAAUAGGCUCCGUACUGCCCAGGGGCAUCUGUGGGAGAGAGGAGGGUGGUGCCAUACCUGCUGCAUCAGGCAUCAAAAUCCCCCGUCAGUUCCCCUGACCCCCACCUCCACGCCAACAUGCAGGACUAGGGGGCUCCGAGCCUGCAGUCCCUGGGGACCCACGGGGGCUGCCAACAGAAUUCAGGGAGCCUAUGACCUUGGAUGGGAAAGCAUUACACCUCAAUUUCACUCACUUCUCACUGAAAUUGAGCAGUUCUUUCAAUGAGAUGUAGGCAAGAAACCAAAGUAGCAGUGGUAGGACCUGCAACUUUGUUACUAGUAUUUGCUUAUCACAUGACAGUAGCUGCAAAUAUUUCAAAAUAUCAUUUACACAUAUUGCUGCUUUGAAAUUGUGGUAGCUACUGAGAUCACCAGAUCUUGUUAUUUGAUGUGUUAAUAAAGAAGCACAUAUAUAGCAAGUCAGGAAACUUAAAA